ACACUUCCCGACACGCCGCGUGAGGCGCUGCCAGCGGCCGGCCGAGGGCGGGCGGACGCGGGAGCUGCGGACGUGAGGCAUGAGCGGCGCCCUCCUCCGGCCCGCGAGCGUCCUGCUGGUUCCCCGAGCGAGGGUCUCGCGGCGCGGGGCCUAGCGGAGGGCAUCGAAGGCCUCCGCGUGCGCACGGGUUGCUGCGGCCGCGCCGGGCGCCGGGGAGGGCGGCGGCCGCCAUGGAGGUGAGCGGGCCGGAAGACGACCCCUUCCUUUCGCAGCUGCACCAGGUGCAGUGCCCCGUGUGCCAGCAGAUGAUGCCCGCCGCGCACAUCAACUCGCACCUGGACCGCUGUCUGCUGCUCCACCCGGCGGGGCACGCGGAGCCCGCGGCCGGGUCGCACCGCGCCGGGGAGCGGGCCAAGGGGCCCUCGCCGCCCGGCGCCAAGAGGCGGCGGCUGUCGGAGAGCUCGGCGCUGAAGCAGCCAGCCACCCCGACGGCAGCCGAGAGCAGCGAGGGCGAGGGUGAGGAGGGCGACGACGGCGGCGAGACCGAGAGCCGCGAGAGCUACGACGCGCCGCCCACACCCAGCGGCGCCCGCCUUAUCCCCGACUUCCCGGUGGCCCGCUCCAGCAGCCCCGGGAGGAAGGGGUCGGGGAAGAGGCCGGCGGCCGCCGCCGCGGCGGGGAGCGCGUCUCCGCGCAGCUGGGACGAGGCGGAGGCGCAGGAGGAGGAGGAGGCCGUGGGCGACGGCGAUGGCGACGGGGACGCGGACGCGGACGGCGAGGACGACCCGGGGCACUGGGACGCGGACGCUGCCGAAGCCGCCACCGCCUUCGGGGCCAGUGGCGGGGGCCGCCCGCACCCCCGGGCGCUGGCUGCCGAGGAGAUCCGACAGAUGCUACAGGGCAAGCCGCUGGCCGACACGAUGCGUCCUGACACGCUGCAGGAUUACUUCGGGCAGAGCAAGGCCGUGGGCCAGGAUACCCUGCUGCGCUCGCUCCUGGAGACCAACGAAAUCCCCUCGCUUAUCCUGUGGGGGCCGCCGGGCUGCGGCAAGACCACUCUGGCUCACAUCAUAGCCAGCAACAGCAAGAAACAUAGCAUAAGGUUUGUGACAUUAUCUGCAACAAAUGCCAAGACAAAUGAUGUGCGAGAUGUCAUAAAACAAGCUCAAAAUGAAAAGAGCUUUUUCAAAAGGAAAACCAUCCUUUUUAUUGAUGAGAUUCAUCGGUUCAAUAAAUCUCAGCAGGACACUUUCCUUCCUCACGUGGAAUGUGGGACGAUCACUCUGAUUGGGGCAACCACUGAAAACCCUUCCUUCCAGGUCAACGCUGCUCUUCUGAGCCGCUGUCGAGUGAUUGUUCUUGAGAAGCUUCCAGUAGAGGCAAUGGUGACUAUUUUAAUGCGAGCGAUCAACUCCCUGGGAAUCCACGUCCUAGACUCUAGCCGUCCCACUGACCCUCUGAGCCACAGCAGCAACAGCAGCUCAGAGCCCGCCAUGUUCAUAGAGGAUAAAGCAGUAGACACCCUGGCUUACCUCAGUGACGGUGACGCCCGAGCUGGGUUGAACGGACUGCAGCUGGCGGUGCUGGCUAGGUUAAGCUCUAGGAAGAUGUUCUGUAAGAAGAGUGGGCAAUCCUAUUCUCCCAGUAGAGUUCUGAUCACAGAGAAUGACGUGAAGGAGGGCCUACAGCGAUCCCACAUUUUAUAUGACCGGGCAGGUGAGGAGCAUUACAACUGCAUCUCCGCCCUGCACAAGUCCAUGCGGGGCUCAGACCAGAACGCCUCCCUCUACUGGCUGGCUCGCAUGCUCGAGGGAGGAGAGGACCCACUCUACGUGGCACGGAGGCUUGUCAGGUUUGCCAGCGAGGACAUAGGUCUGGCAGACCCGUCUGCGUUAACACAAGCGGUUGCUGCCUACCAAGGCUGUCAUUUUAUAGGCAUGCCUGAAUGUGAGGUGCUUCUGGCCCAGUGUGUGGUCUACUUUGCCAGAGCCCCAAAGUCCAUUGAGGUGUACAGCGCCUACAACAACGUCAAAGCCUGCCUGAGGAACCACCAGGGGCCACUGCCCCCCGUGCCCCUGCACCUGAGGAACGCGCCCACUAGGCUGAUGAAGGAUUUGGGCUAUGGCAAAGGCUACAAGUACAACCCCAUGUACAGCGAGCCUGUGGAUCAGGAGUACCUGCCUGAAGAGUUGAGGGGGGUAGAUUUCUUCAAGCAGAGGAGGUGCUGACUCCUCAGGGCACGACAGCAGAAGGAUGUUGCUUUUUUAAGGGAGGGCCAGAAAGAAAGUUAGUGGAUUGCAAAGUUGGUUGCCUGGUGGAAGUUAGAACAGACCAACAUUUUGUGCCAGAAAUUUAAGAGUUCCAUAGGUGGAGGCGCAGUUCUUUCGAAUAAAUGUGUAACUUUGAAAUUGUGUUCAUUUGCACUCGGUGCAGCGGUUAUGCUUAUGAAAAUACCUGGCAGCUUUGUGCAAUGAAUUAAUGUUAUAAGGAAUUAUCUAUUUUGUCAUAGUAUUUAAGUCAUAAUGUCAUUUCAGAAUUCAGUUCUGUAGGAUUUUCUUUUCUUUAAAAAAUGUAUAUUCUGGGUAGUUUUAAUUGGUAAAAAAAUGUAAUUGUGAUUUAAUACUGCAUAGUGUUUUGGGUAUUUUUUUUAUAUGCAAAGGUCUUACGAGCCAAUAAAACUAUUUCAAAGUACUCUUCGAUUCUGUCAUGGUUUUCCUGCCUGGAUGCUAGGUACCAGCGUUGUCACCAUUGCAUUUGGUGGGUGGAUACUGGGAAGGAGAAAUCACCCCAGAUGGGAAGAGUGGGGAGCUUAAGUUAAGAAGUCAGUGUUAUCUUGUUGAAAGUUAACUCUGAUCUCUUUAAAGGAAUACAUAAAGGAAUUCUUUAAAUGGCUUGUGGAAGACUCCAGUAGUCCCAUGCCCAUUUUUUCCCACUUGUCCUGGUUUCUUCUUGCAGCUCCAUAUUUCUAAACAGUCGUUUUUCUUUUACUUUAUGUGUGUCCUGAACACAAAAUACGCCACUCCUUCUGCUCAGUUAAGAGUUAUUUGUCCCUACUGCUACUUCCUCUCCCUCUCCUUAGUUGCAUGUCGUGCAUAUGCCCACAAGGAUGGCCCCUUCAGGUAGUCGGUUCUCCUCCUGCUGUUGCGUGAUCCCUCCUGGGGUCCUCCUGCCAUGUCUGGAAGGCUGCCGGCUGUUGGCCUGGGACGUCCUCUGCCUUUAUUCUGAGUGAGAUGCCCAUUUUCUGGAUGCUCCAUCCCGCCUUACUGGUUUAUUCCGCUAUUUCAGUGCAACCCAUCCUCUAGUAGUUUUAUCAGGCUGGAGGGACUGUAUGUUGCAGAGGCUUGGCCCGACUGGCCUCCCUCCUUCUGUCUGGAGUGGUUGCACUGCAGUGUGCAGUUGCCAUCCCCAGAAUCUCCCUUCAUCAUCACCCUGGAGCUUUCCUCUGCUUCUCCCUGCACCCCAUCUGAUGACAGGACUGACUGCUUUCUGGCACAGGUGGCAUGUACCCUCUAGUAGCUUUAUGGAGCAGGGGUGUGUGGAGGAAAAGUAUUUUUAGACCUCAGGAGACUCAAAAUGCUUUUAUUGUACCUUCAGACGUGUCUGAGGGUUUGGCUAGUAAUAAAUUGUAGGUAAGAAAUUACUUGUGCAUUGUUUUACACUUUCCCACAUUGUUGUCAAGUUUGAAGGCAUCCUGAUGUGUGUGGUCUUUUGUUUGUAACCUCUAUCAACUUGUAGACUCUUCUGUCUUUGCUCCCCGUGUUUUAAAAGUCUGCACUGGGUACUUGUUGGGCCUUUCAAUCUGGAAACUCCUUUCAGUUCUAGGGAAGUUUCUUUUUUUAUUCAAUAAAUUUAUUUAUUUAUGAGACCAACUCUUGCUCUUUUUCCCAGGCUGGAGGGC